CUAAAGAGUUUAACAGCCUCAGUAAUUAAGCACAAAGUAAUACCUUACACCAAAGCCCUUUGCAGAAAGAGAAACCUGGCCAGGCGUGGUGGCUCAUGCCUGUAAUCCCAGAACUUUGCGAGGCUGAGGCAGGUGGAUCACCUAAGGUCAGGAGUUUGAGAUGAGCCUGACCAAUAUGGUGAAACCCUGUCUCUACUAAAAAUACAAAAAUUAGCCAGGUGUGGUGGCAUGCCCCUGUAGUCCCAGCUAUUUGGGAGGCUGAGACAGGAGAAUCGCUUGAACCUGGGAGGCAGAGGUUGCAGUGAGCCAAGAUCACGCCAUUGCACUCCAUCCUGGGCGAGAGAGCAUGACUCCAUCUUACAAAAAAAAAAUUGAUUACUUGAUCCUCCAUUAUAUGUCAAGUAAUGGAGGAUUUACUUUAAGGACACACUUGUGAAAUAGUCCUCUCUGUCUUUACUGGAAGCCAGGCAAACCUUAACCAUCAGGCCUUACAGAACCUGGAAUAGGAGUAUGGUCUGGAUUGAGCAGAUGUGCAUGGCUUGGUGUGCUCUAGGGACUGCAGGAGCUAGAGCACAAGGCUCUUAUUCUCGUGCUUCACCUUCCAUGUGACUCAACUAUUUUGUCAGUUUCUGCUUCCCUUAAGAUCUGUUUUUUUUUUAUGUUACCAAGGUGAACCAUUUACUUCAUUUUACAAUAUCUGGAGAGAAAUGGUCUGAGGCUGUUUAAUUACCAUAGUCCCUUGAGGAGUUUUCCUUCAAGUCACACCAUCGUUGCUGAUUAUCCUAUAUUUUGGCAACUCUUGGGCCAUGGGCACUUCCUAGUCCAAUCAGCUUUGGCCAGAGGCAGAUUCUACUAUACAGACAUGGUCAUCUCCAAAUUAGAGGGAACCCCCAGCUCCAAGUGAAGGGUACAUGUGGACGGUUUCCUUUAUAAAGGGAUGUGUGAUGGUGGGACAGGCAUGUCUGCUGCAGUAGGAAUGUUUCAUUUGGUAGAGAGGAAACAUAAGAAAAAGUAGGAUUGGUACCCACCAUUAUUAUUAAAAAGUAGGAUUGCUACCAGCCAUUAUUAUUAAAAAGUAGGAUUGCUACCCGCCAUUACUAUUAAAAAGUAGGAUUCCUACCCGCCAUUAUUAUUAAAAAGUAGGAUUGGUACCCGCCAUUAUUAUUAAAAAGUAGGAUUGCUACCCAACAUUAUUAUUAAAAAGUAGGAUUGCUACCCUCCAUUAUUAUUAAAAAGUAGGAUUGCUACCCUCCAUUAUUAUUAAAAAGUAGGAUUGCUACCUGCCAUUAUUAUUAAAAAGUAGGAUUGCUACCUGCCAUUAUUAUUAAAAAGUAGGAUUGCUACCUGCCAUUAUUAUUAAAAAGUAGGAUUGCUACCCGCCAUUAUUAUUAAAAAGUAGGAUUGCUACCCGCCAUUAUUAUUAAAAAGUAGGACUGCUACCCGCCGUUAUUUGCACAGCUACCUUAUGAAAGUAGUUUCACGUGUGUCUUAGAUCACUUUAGAGGAAAGAUAUCAGACAAAGAGACCUGAAAUAAAUGGGAAAAACUUUUGACUUAAAUGUAAUAUUCCUCUGACAGUGUACAACGUAAGUGGAGUUGGAAAUUAUGCCAGAGAGUGAGUUUGCCAUCGCCAGGCUUUUACAAAUGUCGUCAUCCCUAUGUAUUGAGCACUGUUUCAGUGUGCAGAUACUGGCUAGUACUUUUUUAAAUAAAGAUUUUAUUUUGAGUAACCUGGCUAUUAGUCAUAACCUGUCUUAAUUCACCUUCCCUAGAAGUAGAACCUGAGAAGGAAUUUGGGUGCAUGUGGUUUAUUGAGUUUACACUCUUAAAAAACAUCACCAAAGAAUGAAGAAAACAGAACAGAGAAGAGCUAAGCAAGAAUGUAAUCAUAGGUAAAAUGCAGUCUUAUUCUGAUUCAGAAGAAUUAUGUAAAAUUUGCACUGGAGAAUUGUUCCAAUCUGAGGCAAGGUAUCUUGGAUUUGUGGCCCCUGCAUCACUCAGUCAUUGGAUGUUUGGGGUGAGGGGUGGUGUCACUCCCCAAGUGUCUCGGGGUGAGCCAGCUCCCAUCAGCCCCAGGUAAUUCUUCCUAGAUCAAGUGUGUAAACUGUUAGCUGCAGCACCUGCCAUAGCCGGGAGAUGGGUAUCCAGCUGGCAAAUGGGAUCUGGGUGGAGCAUCAGCAGCAUCUGCUGCAGGCUUCCUUGAGUCUACCUCAGAGAGCUUGUUGCAGGCCAGAAACUCUGGCUCGUAUAGGCAAAAAGCAGAACUGAUUGGAAGGAAUAGAGGGCUGACUGAUCUGAGAGACAAGAGGACCAUAUCUGGACUAUGGCAGAAGACAAGGCAAUCUUAGAGGACUAAGAGGACCAAGUCUCAGAAGCCUGUCAGUACAGUGAGGGUUUUUAAGCAAUAAUUGCUGGCCAGGACAGCAUUUUGACUGGAUGCCACUGGACAUCAUUGCAGCCAUUCUAAGUGAGUUCCCAUCAUCUCUCCAAAGCCAGCCCUUUGGGUAGAAACACCCAAUUGGCCAAAUGUAGAGCACACAUUUAUCAUUAGCAUGCUUUAAAUGGAGAGAGGAUGAGGCAGCUGCUUUUUUCUUGGAUGGAAGGAAGGCAUUGCAUCUCACCAAUAACUCACAUCAUGCGAUAUUCUUCAGCAAUUGGAAAAGGAGUUUGAUGCUGAAGAGCAAAACCUGAGAGACAGCCAGAGUGUCUCCUGAAAGCUGGCAAAGUGAAGAUUAUUACCCUUAUUUUACGAUUAUAAAAACUGAGGCUCAGAGAAGUAAUUUUAUUCAUUGAUUCAGAGAGAUUAAGUUCAUUCAUUUGCCAAUUAUUUGUCGAGUGUCUGCUAUGGGCUGAGCCUUAUUCUAGGUCCUAGGGAUUCAACACUGAACAAAAUAGGCAAAAAUCCAUGGCCUCAUGCAGUGUACAUUUUUUUUUUUUUUGACAUGGAGUCUUGCACUGUCACCCAGGCUGGAGUGCAAUGGUGCGAUCUCGGCUCACUGCAACCUCCACCUCCCAGAUUCAAGCAAUUCUCCUGCCUCAGCCUCCCAAGCAGCUGGGAUUACAGGCUCCCACCACCACGCCUGGCUAAUUUUUUGUAUUUUUAGUAGAGAUGGGGUUUCACUAUGUUGGCCAGGCUGCUCUCAAACUCCUGACCUCAGGUGAUCCACCCGCCUCAGCCUCCCAAAGUGCUGGGAUUACAGGCAGGAGCCACUGUGCCCAGCCUGCAGUGUACAUUUCUAUGUGGUGUGUGUUGGGGGAGAGGGGGUUGAGACAAAAAAUAAUAGGUAAAUAAAACACAUAGUACAUCAGACGGUGACAAAUAUUAGAAAGAAAAAAUAAAUCAGGAAAGGUGAGUGGGUUGGGGUGUGGUGGCUAUAUUAUGGAGAUGUUUCCAUUUUAAAUAGGGCAGUCAAAGUAGUCCCUGCUAAAACAGUGACAUUUGAGCAAAGACCUGAAGGAAGUAAGGGAAUGAGCUAUGUGACUGUCUGUGGAAAUGUCCUAGGCAGAGCGAACAGCAGGUGCAAGAUGCCCUGAGGCCUGCAUGCAACUGGCAAGCUAAGGGACCCACGUGGAGGCUAAUAUGGUUGGGGAAGAGGGAGCAAGGGGGAGCCGCAGGAGGAAAAAGCCAGGAGGUGGCUGGGCCUGGAUCAUGGGGGCCUUGGAGCCCAUAAAAUGUUUUGAGGAAGGGAUUGACAUUAUUGGAAUUACAUUUCUAAGGGUAGAAGGAUGGACAGAAGCAGAAAAACUGGUUAGGAAGUUUCUGCAAUAAAUUAAGUAAGUGAUAAUAGAGUCUGGGAUUAGGGUGGCAGCUGUGGAGGUACUGAAAAAUAAUAUUUUUGCUAUGUUGUAGGCUGCACAGUGGCCCUCUAACAUGUCUGUGUCCUAAUUCCUAUAAGGCAGAGACUUUGCAGAUGUGGUUAGAGAUCUUGGGAUGGGGAGAUUAUUCUGGGUUAUCCAUGUGGUCCCUAUAUAAACAUAAGGGUCCUUAUAAGAAAAAACAAGCAGAGUUAGAAAGAGAGAAGGUGAUUAUUCAUAGAAGUCAGGUAUGGAAGUGUCAAGGGUCAAGGAUAUGGAUACAGUGAAAGCAUUCAUCGAUAGAUAAAUGGAUAAAGAAAAUAGAAUGUUAUUGAGCUUUAAAAAAGAGUAAAAUCCUGUCAUUUGUGACAACAUAGAUGAACACAGAGGACAUUAUGCUAAGUGGAAUAAGCCAAGCACAGAAAGACAAAUACUGCCUGAUCUCACUUAUGUGUAAAAUCUGAAGAUAUUGAACUCAUAGAAGCAGAGUGUAGAAUUUGGUUAGCAGGGGUUGGAGGGUGAGGGAAAUGGGGAGAUGUUGGUCAGAGUACAAAGUUUUAGUUAUGCAGGAUGAAUAAGUUUGGAGAUCUCAUGUACAGCAUGGUGACUAUAGUUAAUAAUACUGUAUUGUAAACUUGAAAUUUGCUGAGAGAGUAGAUGGUAAAUAGUCUUACCACAAAAUGAAAAGUAACUAUGAGAAGUGAUGGUAUGUUAAUGAGCUUCAUUGUGGUAAUCAUUUCACAAUGCAUAACUAUAUGAAAACAUCACAUUGUACACCUUAAAUAUAUACAAUAUUUAUUUAUCAAUUGUAACUCAACAAAGCUGGAAAAGGAAGAAGAGAGAAGGUGAUGUGAAGAUGGAAGAAACAGAGACAGAAAAGGUGCUAUGCUUGCUUCUGGCUUUGACGAGUGAAGAAGGGGCCAGGAGCCAAAGAAUGUAGUCAGCUUCUAGAAGCCGAAAAAAUCAAAGAAAAGGUUUUUCUCUUAGAUCCUCCAGAAGGAACACAGCCCUACAGAUGCCUGACCUCCAGAACUAUAAGUAAAAAAAAAAAAAAAUUAUGUUGUGUUAAGCCCCUGUGUUUGCAGUGAUUUGUUACAGCAGCGAAAGGAAACAAACACGUGGGUUUUGGAGUUAGAGUCAGUGAUGUUUACCCAUGGAUGAGACGCAGAGAGGGUCAGGGAUAACGUUACAAGUUUGUGAAGAGCAACUGGAAGGAUGGAGUGCCUUUUACUGGGGAAAACUUGUUUGGGGUGAAUUUAAGUCCAAGCCCCUGGCGAUACCCUUUCUGCUCGGGCUAUGCUAAGAGGAUAAACCAGGACAAAAUUCAUGGGAGAUGCACCAGCUUAGCUGGUCAGAUGAGUAUGUCCACUGUCAUCAUCCUUCCCCUAAUUUUACACCCUCUUUGCAGCCUCUAUCUAUCAGUAUUUCCUCGUUGUUCUUUGAUGGUAGCAGGCAGCACAGAGCUCAAUGAAAUUAGACAUAUAUUUCUUAUUUUAAGGUACAGCUGAGAAAAUGUCUAGGAAAUAAAAGUUGCUUUGAUGUAAGCUGCAUUAUCUGGAGGCUUGUUAAUGGUCUGUCACUGGGGUCCUCAGGUUGAGGAAUGGAUUCCUUAAAUUGAUAAUCACUGAAAUAGUCCCCAACGACCAUAGUGCUGCUUUGGUUAUCCUCAGCCAGUGACAAAAGUCAUACUAUUGUAGUCAAAGAAGCUAUGCCAGGGAGUUGGAGCGCCUGGUUUUGACUGGCUUUGCUAUUCACCUGCUGUCACUCUCUCUUUUUGAGCCUCAGCUUCCCCAUUUGUAAAUUGAGAGUGCUACAGCCAAUGUUUUCAAAGAGGCUUCAUGGGGCUGCUUCGCCUUGCUAUUUGUUAUGCAUCUUAGAGAGAAGCUUGAUCGAGCAUUAAGCCAUCCAGAUCUCAGCAUUGUUCUGUCUCAGGUCCUGAGGAGCAGGCACUGACCUACUUCUCCUGCCUUCUUUUCCCUGCUGUCCUAUUGGUCUUUAUUCUGACCCCAGACCUGUCAUUGCUCAGGAUGCAGUUAAGAGGCCUUACUUCUAUUCCGAGUGGCCAAUGACUCACAUGUCCACGGGACUGAGCAGUGAGGACAGGCUCCAUUCGACAGAGUCCAAGGCAGAUGGUCAUGCUUCCUUUCCAGAAUGAACAUCAAGUGCCAGGAACUCAGUGAGGGGCACUCUCCUUCUGACUUGGAGCUCUGUGAGGCAGCCACACAGGCCAGGUUCCGGCCACCUUCUGUUCUGGUUUGCCUAAUGAUGCUUUUGGCGAAAGACAAGGAAGAACAGCAAAAGCAAAGAAGGAAGCGAUUCAUCUGUUAAGGGAGCGUAGCAAGCAUCCUUGACCCUCCCGAAGGAAGUUUCCAUGAAAAUAAAACACAAGCAGAACACCAUGCUGUUGCCUCCCAGGAGGAUGACAAAUUUGUGGUAUGAAUGCCCUCCCUGUCCUCCUUCCUAAGCCACGCUGAUGAGUUGGGACCUGUAGGACCCAUGUGACAGGAGUUAUUAUGACUCCCUCCAUUCCUUCUCCUUCCGGCUGUAGCAAAUCUGGCCUGUCUGAUAGCACAAGACUGAAUGACUGGUGCUGAGUAUUAUACAAUGUAUGUUGUAGAGACUAACGAAGACUUAAAUAAAUAAGCAAGUGCAUUUAGCAAGUGCAUCCUUUUAGGAUGUUAUUUACUGUGGGACUUUAUAUAUGUCGCAUCAUUCUUUUGCUUCUCACGGGGAGCACGUUUAUCAAACAAAGAUUCUGGCCAAAUCUUUUAUAGUCAAAAAGAUAUUGAAUGUCAACAUCAUAGUCAUUUACCAUUGGAGGGUCCCUUAAACCACUUAAGACAGGAAAUAGAAAUCAUCAUUAUUUCCUGGCUUUCGAACUGCUCUUACCCUGUUUCACUUACUUAGUGCACCACACAGUCCUGUGGACUAGGUUUCACUAUUAUUCUCUUUAUGCAGCUGGGGGAACUGAGCGGUUGAGGGAUCUAAAGCAUUUUAAAAACUUGCAGUGGGGCUGGGCGCGGUGGCUCACACCUGUAAUACCAGCACUUUGGGAGGCCAAGGCAGGCGGAUCACCUGAGGUCAGGAGUUCAAGUCUAGCCUGGCCAAUAUGGUGAAACCCCGUCUCUACUAAAAAUACAAAAAUUCGCCAGGCGUGGUGGCUUGCGGCUGUAAUCCCAGCUACCCAGGAGGCUGAGGCAGGAGAAUUGCUGGAACCCGGGAGGCUGAGGCUGCAGUGAGCUAAGAUUGCGCCACUGCACUCCAGCCUGGGCGACAAAGUAAUACUCCAUCUCAAAAAAUAAAAAAAAAUAAUAAGUAAAUAAAUAAAUAAAUUGCAAUGGGAAGAGCAGACACCACUGCUCUUGAAAUAUCCUUCAGCCUUUCCAUGACUGUGGAGUUUCACCAUCCCCAGCCCAUCUCGUUCAGUUUGUCUCCAUCUUGGGUUCUGUCUCCUUCCUUCACUUCCUAGCUCUGCCGUUUUCGUUUUGCACUCCCUCAUCCGAAGUCUAAAACAAAAUUGCUCUAAUUUCACCACAGUUGUUUUGCCCACUUGUCUGAAGCUGUCCUCAAAAGUAUCUUUUCUAUCCAAAGAGCUCAUCAAGUUUUUUUUUUGUUUUUUUUUGUUUUUGUUUUUUUUGGUCUUUUUGCCCCAGACAAAGGCAAUUUUCCUCUUAAGAGGAAUUAUUCUGAAAGCUGUUAAAAAAGUGACAUUUGCUGUCUCCGGGAUUUUCUUUGGAGUAGCAGGCAGUUGUUCCUAUGAUCAUGAAGAUGUGCUCCUCUCACACCACAUGUGCACCCUGCUGCCCUGGGUUUGUGCCAUUUUGUUUUCACAACUUUUGGUUUCAAUGCUAAAUCAUAAUAAACUUGUAAAAAGUUUAACAUGAUAAUUCGUUUGAGCCAUACACAUAAAAAAAGACAGUUAUUUUUUUCAGGUUUUAAAAUGAAGAGAAAUGCAAGAGCAGACCCAACUCUGGGAAUUAUGACAGGUUUCACAAGGAAGGGGUCUCAGGUGUGUGGCAUAUCCUACCAAGUGGAGGUGGCAUUUCAGGUAGAGGGAAUAAGAUAGGCAACGGCAAAGAUGCAUAAACUAGCAUGGUAUGUCAAGAUAAUAGAGACGGAGAAUUGAGGCGAAAGUGAGAGAUGAUUCUGGAGGAGCAGGUUGGGAAGAGGGAAGGACAGAGUCCUAUCCCCUGUCCUUAUGAUCUCGUACAACUCCCACAUAAACUAUAGAGUACAGCACUAUCUAACGCAGCAAUAUUUGCUCGUGCUGAUGAUGUUAUUUUUGUGUUCUUGUUAUUACUAGCAAUCUGAAGUCAGCCAGGAGUCCCAAACUGGAAUGAUCUGAUUUCAGUGGCUGGUGUGGUUUAAUUCUCUGGCAUGUUGUUCUUAGUAUUAGGAGUGCAGUGUGGAAUGGGCAAUGAGAAAUUGGGCACCUGUUUCCAAUUUCAGGCACUGCAGAUUCAUACGCACAGUCCUGGGGUAAAGGUUUUUGAGGUAGAUAAUGCUUUCAUGGAGUGUUUGUGUAUGUGUGUGUGUGUGUGUGUGUGUGUGUGGUGGUGGGGGUAGGGGUUCACGAGCUGCAAAGAUCCACUGUCAUCAGUUUUCACGAGCAUUUCAAAGAAGUAUGUGUGUGAGGGGUUGGCUUUCUCAGAGAUUGUCACUCUAUGAUUAAUCUCAUAAUAAAUCCUAAAAUUCAAAUUCCAAAGGAAGGCCUUGUAUGGUGGAUGGUGUGUGGGUGGUCGGGGGGUCAACCGAAUGCUAAAGAGAAAGUAGGCAGAGCUGUUAGCCUGAGCUGAGAUGGGCUGCAGCCCUCCCGGAAGCUUAAGUAUGUCAGCACCUCUGGGAGAAUGGGUCAUGAGUUGACUCUUCUGAAGGAGAAACGUGGAGUGAAUGAAAAGAUCCCAGUCAAUUGGCAGGUUGACUAGAGAUUUGAUGGGGUGAUUUCUUCUUCACAGUGGGAAGAUGAUCUCACAUGGCAGUGAGGAGGGAAGAACCCUGUGCAAGUGAUUUAGAUGAUUGAAGAUAAUUUUUUGGCUGGGGAAAGAUGUGAUAAAAUUUGGUGCUCAGUAAAUCCCUCCUCCACUUUAAUUGGAAGUGUUGGGAUCAGCCAUCUAUUUUGUGCUGUUGUAAUUUUCUUUACUUCCAUUUAGGUUUUUCUCAGCAUUUAGUAAAUUUCAUUUUGAAUGUAUCAGCCUGUCUCAGUUGUGCAAAGGAAAACAAGGAGAAAGAUUAUGUUUACCUUGAGCUGAGAAGAAAAGAGGGAUAGCGUUUCUCUCUCAUCCUCCCCAACCCAACUCCCCAACCCAGGGAGACGGGGACUAGGCUUGGUGGCGGCUACAGGAAUCAAAAUAAAAGAACUCCAGGGAAAGGCAAAAGCUCAGAGGGAAGUGUUGGAAUGCUGACCUUGCCCCACCCUGUUUACCUGCCAGACCUGUUUCCAAGGAUACUCUUCUCUGGGGGAUGAAAAUUUAGAUCAUCACACGGAAAAUACUUAUCGUGUUCUUCAUAUUCAAGGCUGAAGAAAUGUCAACAAUUGGGAGUUUUGAAGGAUUCCAGGCUGUGUCUCUGAAGCAAGAGGGAGAUGACCAACCCUCUGAGACUGACCACCUAUCGAUGGAGGAAGAGGACCCGAUGCCAAGACAGAUUUCAAGGCAGUCAAGUGUGACCGAAUCAACUCUUUACCCCAAUCCUUAUCAUCAGCCUUAUAUCUCACGGAAGUACUUUGCUACACGGCCGGGGGCCAUUGAGACUGCCAUGGAAGACUUGAAAGGUCACGUAGCUGAGACUUCUGGAGAGACCAUUCAAGGCUUCUGGCUCUUGACAAAAACGGAUCCAUUAAGCCAGCACCAAGGAGAACAUCUUGACACUUUAUGGAAUUUCAAAAAGAUAGACCACUGGAACAAUGAGAAGGAGAGAAUUCUACUGGUCACAGACAAGACUCUCUUGAUCUGCAAAUACGACUUCAUCAUGCUGAGUUGUGUGCAGCUGCAGCGGAUUCCUCUGAGCGCUGUCUAUCGCAUCUGCCUGGGCAAGUUCACCUUCCCUGGGAUGUCCCUGGACAAGAGACAAGGAGAAGGCCUUAGGAUCUACUGGGGGAGUCCGGAGGAGCAGUCUCUUCUGUCCCGCUGGAACCCAUGGUCCACUGAAGUUCCUUAUGCUACUUUCACUGAGCAUCCUAUGAAAUACACCAGUGAGAAAUUCCUUGAAAUUUGCAAGUUGUCUGGGUUCAUGUCUAAGCUUGUUCCAGCUAUCCAGAAUGCCCACAAGAAUUCAACUGGAUCUGGAAGAGGAAAGAAACUGAUGGUGUUAACUGAACCCAUUUUGAUUGAGACCUACACAGGGCUGAUGUCAUUCAUUGGAAACCGCAACAAACUUGGCUAUUCCCUUGCCCGUGGGAGUAUUGGUUUUUGAGAGUCUUUUUGGUACCAUAAGCAUAUCAUCCACAGAUAUGUCACUUUGAAAAUUCCAGUUUGACCCACGCUAUUUUUGGACUGAAACAAUUAAUUAUUUUUAAAUGACGCUUUAUGAUUUAGAAAUUUAGUAUUUCCGAAAAUUUAAAAGCUUGAUUGGACUGAUAGAUACACACUUUAGACCUCAUACAAGAAUAAUCAAAUUUUCUUAAAACUAGAAAAUAAAUGCUGCUGAGCCUAUCAAAUACUGUUAUCAAAUGAGUGCCUGAUCAUCAACUCAGGAAAGAAGACUCUAAGUCCUGUUGCUUCAGCUCUCUAAAUGUAGGCUUUUUUUUUUUUUUUUUUUUAGGUCUUGGUCUUCAGCCCUCUUAUCCUGAUUUAUUCUCUCAUUGGGGUCUCACUGUCUCUAGUAUUUUAGCUACCACUUGAUAAGGAUGACUUCCAAAUUUAUAUUCCCAUUCCCAAUAUUUAUUCCAAGACUCAGUUUUGCAUUUCUGACUGCUAAUCAUCUAUAUAUCAGUGUCCCAGUGGCCUCUUAAUUGAGCAUUAUCAAAAUCCUGUGGUAUUUAUAUGGUCCCAGUUAUCCAUCCCUGAAGUCUGUCAAUUUUGAUUUCUCUAAAUUCCUUGCCAUGACAUCCUAUAUAUGAUCACAUCUCUAUACGGCUUAGCAUUGUAUUCCGAUGCCCAGAUGUCAAACUUGAAGCUCAUUCUCUUAUCAAAAUUGUUCAUGUAUUCCUCCUUUCCAUUCUUAUAGCUGUAUUAUUAGAUCAGGUUUUUAAUUCUGCUCAACCAAUUAUUACCACAGCCUGUUAAAUGGAAUCCCUACUCCAAGGCUGACUGUUUCAAUCUAUCCUACACUUGGUUUCUAGCUCAUUUACUUAUACCAUCUUUUGUUCAAAUAUAUAUUUUUUAAUAACAGACCUUUUUCUUCUAAAGAAAUCUUUUGUAGAAGCAGCAUAUACGAAGCAGAUAAAAGUAGGUUCAAUGCGGUUGGAGUGAAGAUGAGAAUGCCACAGGCAUCUUUCUUUCUAGGCCUCAGAGGUGCUGCAUAUGGAAUGUCCAUGGAUCGCAGAGGGUUUUGAAGACCAUGUUUUCAAAAACACUGUCUUAACACUCUAUUGUCAUUGCUCUUUUCCCUCUUAUUUCCUCUUUGUCUCUUCCCGACUUAGAUCUAAUUUUCAACAACCCAGGAAAUUAUCUCAUAUGUUUGCAUCUCUCAAGUUUCUUUUCUUUUUUCUUUCAGAGUCUUAUUUUAUCUAAAUUUAUGUAGAAAAAAAAGCUUUGAAUGUUGACUACAUAGACAUUACUACAAUAAGCUUUUUGCCUUUCCCAAGACUCAAAAUUGACACAUCUUUGUUGAUGUUUAAGUUGAAAUUCCAGCCAACUUUUUUUUGACUUUUAUGUGAAGUUUAAAGUCUUUUCUUUGAAAAGCUUGCUUCCUCAAUUUCAAAGAUUUGUCCUCUGAUAUAUUUAUAAACAUCAAUUUAAUGCAGACAUUCAAACCCUAAACCUUGAAUAACUCUUAUUUUAUUUUGUCUUUGUUUACUUCCAUUAAUUUUUUUUUCUUUCCCUCUCUUCCGCCUUUACAGCACCCACUUUUUCUUCCCCCCAUGAUGGCAAAUAUUGUUAUAGUCCCCAAGGCAGGGAACUUCUAUUCAGACUGUAAAAGGAAAUGUUGAAAUCCAUAGCUGUCCUGUCAACAGUAGUGGAAUGAAAAGUCGUUGGAUUGUUUUGGCACUGGUUCUGAAGCAGGCAUAAUUGGCAAAUUAUUAUAAUACUGCUGCCCGAAAAUCCCCAUUUGCCUCAAGAUAGUGGCAUUUAUUGGCAGAAGCCUCUGAAAUGUCCAGCACAUUCUUUUGAGUUACCAUUUAAGGAUCAGCCUGACAAUCGACUUCUCUCUGCACAUUUGCCCCCUUUGUAACCUAAGCCAGACUGUUCCCAAAUGACCUUCUAAAGGACACAGUGCACCAUCAUCAAUGGAAACAGUUCAGAAAGGAUGACAGGAGGGAGAUGUUUCUUAGUUCUGAGAGCCAGUCUGUAACAAUGGGAUAAGCAUUUAAUGGAAUCAAAGCUGUUUUGCAUAAAGAGUGAACUCAGAGACGACAAGAGGGUCUUUAUGAAUUCCCUUCACAUUUUGUAAAAACUGUCAUAUAUAGGCUAUCCCCUUAAUUGAUAAAUGGGAUCUAGAAAGCGGUAUUAUGACCAGAGGGUGAGAAGAUUUAGGAAUUUGGAUAGCAGUUCAAGAUAAGAAAGAACUUCUUAUAGUUAUAAAUUUUCAAUGAUGGAAUGGGUUGCUUCUUUAAACAGUGAGCCCACCAUCACUUGGUAUGUUCAAGGAAAGACUAGAUAAAGUCGAUAUUGUGAGAGGAAUUGCUGUAUGAUACCGUUUGGAGAAAUGAUUGACAUAAUCUUUUAAGGCCGGUGACCCUAUCAUUUUCCAAAUAAUUGUUGCUAGUACUUAGUUAAUUAGACCCAUUUUUUUCUUAGGAAAGAGUUGGAUCAAUCAUGGGAGACCCUGAAAAAUUUCCUUACCUUUCCUAAGGUUUAAUUUCCUCUUCUGCGAAAUGGAGACAAUUAUAUUACUUUUGCUUAUUUCAUAAAGAUCUUGUGAGGAUUCAAUGAAAUGAGGUUAAAUUCUUUUAUUAAACAGAAAGUUUUGAGUAUUUGCCUAGAGAGUGAUGUGACUUUUGCAGCAGAAGGUGGGAAAACAUCCAAGGGAACUACAUUUCCUCCAGAAAUUGUUUCUUCAUUACCAUCGACCUACUGAUUAUGGUUUUCUCAUUUUACACUUGGUGUUCUUACUUGGGAUCUUUGUCCUUAAGCUCAACAGGGAGCCACAACCCAGGGGACCUAUGUGUACACUUGGAGUUUUUAUCAGACUAUCAUUUGAACUUACCACUACAGUUUAGCAAAUGGCAUGAUGAGUUUGAUUGAUAAUAGGAGUAGACGCAAGAUACAUUAAGUAGAGUACAAAGCAUUUCAUAACCAAAAUGUCAUGGUUGGAGGUCUUCAUUAUUCGGUCUUUAUCUCAUUCAGGAAUUUCCACUUGAAAAAUCUCUGAUAAGCUUUAUUUCAGAAACUGCUUGAACAGCUCCACUGACAAAUGCCUCACUAUCUUCUGAUACAUCGUAGGCAGUUCUGAGGGUGAGAAAGUUCAAAGCAGAUAGAUGUUUUAACACAACAGGAGGACUUUUAAACAAUCACCAGGACUCACUCCUCGGUGGUCAAUUGGGCCUGUUUGGAGGCCUGACCUUUGGUCAUCUUAAGGUCAUCUAAGGCAGAAAAGAGAAGCUCACUUAUAAGUUGGCACUUCUGAAUCAUUUGCCUUGAGGUCCAUUUUUUAUUCAGCCUUUGUUUAAACCUUCUUAGGAAGCCAGUUUGUAGAGUUCUGGGGAUAAGAAGGCAGAAAAACCAUGUCAAUUCAGUGCUUUUAUUUCACAGAAAAUGAAGCAAAGGCCUAGAAACUAGAAAGACAUUUCUCAAAAAGAAGAUGGUGAACUUUUGGAAAUACUGAGAUUAGACUACAUUUUCCAAUUUCUAUCCCUAGCCCACUGCUCUUUCCAAUAUAAUAUCUGUAUUCCAUGGGAAAGACAUGCCAUCUGAAUUGAUGUAUCGUAGUUGUUGAGAUAAUUUUGAAAUGAGAAAACAAUAGGGCACAGUCGUUUGGGAAGAAUUUCCAGAAAUUGCCAUCAUUUUCUUAAAGGCUAAGGACACUUAUAGAGCUCUCCGAUUUCCUAUCUGAUAAAAAAAGCCCAAACAAAGCUGCGGAAGCUGGCAGAGCCAGCAGAUAUUUUGUAAGGCAGCUUCACCUCUGCUGGCAUUUUGUGGGGCAGGAGAGGGGGAGGGCAAAGGUAUUAAAUUUAGGCUUAAAAGCUCCUCAGAAAUUCUUUACACACAAGAGACCAAGUUGGAGAAAAGAAGAUGACUUGUGCCAAGGGGAAGAAAGAGAGAGACUAAUGCCUGUGGUUUUCAAAGGUUAACAACAACAUAAAAAAGCCAAGGUAUUUGCACAGGGAUGAAUGCUCAUUGGCUCUUGGCCAACAAUUAUACAAGGGCUUGUGCCCACAUCCUGUAGCUGUGGUUUAGGGACGCUGCUCAUGAGUGACUUCUUAUGCUUAGUGGCAGGAAACUUUAGUCACUGAUGUGUAAACUCACCUUUGGUCUGCACCUCCCACAACGUGCUCCGAAAGCAGUUAGGGGACUAGGCCUCUUGAUUUCCUUGUAGAUACCAGUUCCCCAGAAGCUAAGGAAAAACUCUGAGGCCUUGGAGUUACUGAGAGUGGACCAAUACUUGUCUUAUUCUACCUGAUUUUGGCAACUGCUUAGGGUUCUUCUGUAUCCACAAAAAGGAAUUAUGAUAUCCUCUGCUAAACCCUCUCUUUAGCCUCAAAGCCCAAGACCAAAAAAAAUGAGCCAUAUUUCAUUGCAGGCCUGCUGCCAAUGUGAAAUAUAAGGAAUAAAGUCAUGAGACUGCUUCUCAACCUA